AACUGACCUGAUUACCAUCUGCAGCCACGAGAAGCAAAGUUGACAUUUCUGGAUCACUCUCCCCAGACGCGUCACUUGCCCACAAGCGGGACACGGCAGUCUCGCUGAGCCAGCUGUGCAGAGGGACAGAUGGAAGAAAGCUAGAGAUGCUGCUUCGUGGGCGCUGAAGUUGCAGAACUUGGGCUGGUUUUCUUUCUUCCCAUCCCCCCUCCUCCUGACAAACCACAUCUUGACUCAGAUGGUCGAAAGAAAAACUCUUUCAGUUAUUUGAUAUUUGGGAACCCUCCAGGAGACCAUAACUUAUUUUUGAGGGAGGCUCCUUCUCUCCCUUUGCUGGGAACACACACACACACACACACACACACACACACACACACACACACACACAGCUGUACACCAUGGUGGUUCAGGCUGCAGUGGCUCCGAAUAGAUCCCAAAGACUUUUACUGAAAAUUCCUUAUGGAUCUCUGAGAAGGCGCAGCGUUGAAAGGAUGACGGAGGGCCGCCGAUGUCAAGUACAUCUUCUUGAUGACAGGAAGCUGGAACUCCUAGUACAGCCCAAGCUGUUGGCCAAGGAGCUUCUUGACCUUGUGGCUUCUCACUUCAAUCUGAAGGAAAAGGAGUACUUUGGAAUAGCAUUCACAGAUGAAACGGGACACUUAAACUGGCUUCAGCUAGAUCGAAGAGUAUUGGAACAUGACUUCCCUAAAAAGUCAGGACCCGUGGUUUUAUACUUUUGUGUCAGGUUCUAUAUAGAAAGCAUUUCAUACCUGAAGGAUAAUGCUACCAUUGAGCUUUUCUUUCUGAACGCGAAGUCCUGCAUCUACAAGGAGCUUAUUGACGUUGACAGCGAAGUGGUGUUUGAAUUAGCUUCCUAUAUUUUACAGGAGGCAAAGGGAGAUUUUUCUAGCAAUGAAGUUGUGAGGAGUGACUUGAAGAAGCUGCCAGCCCUUCCCACCCAAGCCCUGAAGGAGCACCCUUCCCUGGCCUACUGUGAAGACAGAGUCAUUGAGCACUACAAGAAACUGAACGGUCAGACAAGAGGUCAAGCAAUCGUAAACUACAUGAGCAUCGUGGAGUCUCUCCCAACCUACGGGGUUCACUAUUAUGCAGUGAAGGACAAGCAGGGCAUACCAUGGUGGCUGGGCCUGAGCUACAAAGGGAUCUUCCAGUAUGACUACCAUGAUAAAGUGAAGCCAAGAAAGAUAUUCCAAUGGAGACAGUUGGAAAACCUGUACUUCAGAGAAAAGAAGUUUUCCGUGGAAGUUCAUGACCCACGCAGGGCUUCAGUGACAAGGAGGACGUUUGGGCACAGCGGCAUUGCAGUGCACACGUGGUAUGCAUGUCCGGCAUUGAUCAAGUCCAUCUGGGCUAUGGCCAUAAGCCAACACCAGUUCUAUCUGGACAGAAAGCAGAGUAAGUCCAAAAUCCAUGCAGCACGCAGCCUGAGUGAGAUCGCCAUCGACCUGACCGAGACGGGGACGCUGAAGACCUCGAAGCUGGCCAACAUGGGUAGCAAGGGGAAGAUCAUCAGCGGCAGCAGCGGCAGCCUGCUGUCUUCAGGUUCUCAGGAAUCAGAUAGCUCGCAGUCGGCCAAGAAGGACAUGCUGGCUGCCUUGAAGUCCAGGCAGGAAGCUCUGGAGGAAACCCUGCGUCAGAGGCUGGAGGAACUGAAGAAGCUGUGUCUCCGAGAAGCUGAGCUCACGGGCAAGCUGCCAGUAGAAUAUCCCCUGGAUCCAGGGGAGGAACCACCCAUUGUUCGGAGAAGAAUAGGAACAGCCUUCAAACUGGAUGAACAGAAAAUCCUGCCCAAAGGAGAGGAAGCUGAGCUGGAACGCCUGGAACGAGAGUUUGCCAUUCAGUCCCAGAUUACGGAGGCCGCCCGCCGCCUAGCCAGUGACCCCAACGUCAGCAAAAAACUGAAGAAACAAAGGAAAACCUCGUAUCUGAAUGCACUGAAGAAACUGCAGGAGAUUGAAAAUGCAAUCAAUGAGAACCGCAUCAAGUCUGGGAAGAAACCCACCCAGAGGGCUUCGCUGAUCAUAGACGAUGGAAACAUUGCCAGUGAAGACAGCUCCCUCUCAGAUGCCCUUGUUCUUGAGGAUGAAGACUCUCAGGUUACCAGCACAAUAUCCCCCCUACAUUCUCCUCACAAGGGACUCCCUCCUCGGCCACCGUCGCACAACAGGCCUCCUCCUCCCCAGUCCCUGGAGGGACUCCGACAGAUGCACUAUCACCGCAACGACUAUGACAAGUCACCCAUCAAGCCCAAAAUGUGGAGUGAGUCCUCUUUAGAUGAACCCUAUGAGAAGGUCAAGAAGCGCUCCUCUCACAGCCAUUCCAGCAGCCACAAGCGCUUCCCCAGCACAGGAAGCUGUGCGGAAGCCGGCGGAGGAAGCAACUCCUUGCAGAACAGCCCCAUCCGCGGCCUCCCGCACUGGAACUCCCAGUCCAGCAUGCCGUCCACGCCAGACCUGCGGGUCCGGAGUCCCCACUACGUCCAUUCCACGAGGUCGGUGGACAUCAGCCCCACCCGACUGCACAGCCUCGCACUGCACUUUAGGCACCGGAGCUCCAGCCUGGAGUCCCAGGGCAAGCUCCUGGGCUCGGAAAACGACACCGGGAGCCCCGACUUCUACACCCCGCGGACUCGUAGCAGCAACGGCUCAGACCCCAUGGACGACUGCUCGUCGUGCACCAGCCACUCGAGCUCGGAGCACUACUACCCGGCGCAGAUGAACGCCAACUACUCCACGCUGGCCGAGGACUCGCCGUCCAAGGCGCGCCAGAGGCAGAGGCAGCGGCAGCGGGCGGCGGGCGCACUGGGCUCAGCCAGCUCGGGCAGCAUGCCCAACCUGGCGGCGCGCGGGGGUGCGGGGGGCGCGGGGGGCGCGGGGGGCGGUGUGUACCUGCACAGCCAGAGCCAGCCCAGCUCGCAGUACCGCAUCAAGGAGUACCCGCUGUACAUCGAGGGCGGCGCCACGCCCGUGGUGGUGCGCAGCCUGGAGAGCGACCAGGAGGGCCACUACAGCGUCAAGGCUCAGUUCAAGACGUCCAACUCCUACACGGCGGGCGGCCUGUUCAAGGAGAGCUGGCGCGGCGGCGGCGGCGACGAGGGCGACACGGGCCGCCUGACGCCGUCGCGAUCGCAGAUCCUGCGGACUCCGUCGCUGGGCCGCGAGGGCGCCCACGACAAGGGCGCGGGCCGUGCCGCCGUCUCAGACGAGCUGCGCCAGUGGUACCAGCGUUCCACCGCCUCGCACAAGGAGCACAGCCGCCUGUCGCACACCAGCUCCACCUCCUCGGACAGCGGCUCGCAGUACAGCACCUCCUCCCAGAGCACCUUCGUGGCGCACAGCAGGGUCACCAGGAUGCCCCAGAUGUGCAAGGCCACGUCAGCUGCCUUACCUCAAAGCCAGAGAAGCUCGACACCGUCAAGUGAAAUUGGAGCCACCCCCCCAAGCAGCCCCCACCACAUCCUAACCUGGCAGACUGGAGAAGCAACAGAAAACUCACCCAUUCUGGAUGGGUCUGAGUCUCCACCUCACCAAAGUACUGAUGAAUAGAGGAGCUACAAUGAUAGCUGUUUCCUGGAUUCCUCCCUCUAUCCAGAACUAGCUGAUGUCCAGUGGUACGGGCAGGAAAAAGCCAAGCCCGGGACCCUCGUGUGAGCCAGCCCGGCCUAAUCUGACCGCCUCAACGCCAUUCUGAGAUCACCUCACUGCCUCUCAUUUGCCUUACCCAGACGCACCGUCACCCUGCACCAGCUUUGGCCCUCAGCACUUUUUUUCUCCUGUCUCCGCAUUCCCUCCCCCUUGAAAACCUGACUGAGGAGACAUUCUGGAAGGUUCCGGUCCCACUGUGUGUCCCCUGGCGCUCUUGCCCAUAGAGAGCCAGACACCAAUCCUCAAUGGCACCUUGGUGGCUUCCCUCUGCCAUGACAGCCCCUAGGCCAGGAACCAUCAGGGGGGCCAGCCGGCAUCCAAUUCCUGCGGAUAAGUAGCGUUGGGAGAGAACGGGAAAGGGGACUUGAGUUACAGGGUGACCCAGAAAGACGAUUCAGCUGUGUCCAGCCUGCCACCCAUACGUAGGCCAACCAAGCACUUCAUGAAGAGGAGGCCUCGUGGCAUAUUCAGUUUACACCUGAAAUAUUCCUUGAUGGGACAGCUUGUGGGGAUGGCUAUGGGGGAAGGGGAGGUUGAGAAAGGAAGUUCUCGACACCAGAAAUGCAUCGGAGGACCACAAUCAGUUCUAUGCUGCCAAAGAUUAAAAAUAAAUAAAAACAUAAAAAAUUAAGAGGGGCCAAGAGGAAGACAUUCUUUCUGCAAGGAAAUUUCUUUUAAAUUCUGAACUGCUACUACACACAAGUGAAAGUCAACCCUAUGUAAACUGGUGUCCUCUCUCUAGCCCUCUCCCUUACUGGCCCACUUCUCUCUCCGUAGAGAGCCUGAAAAACUGCCCCAAUGCCACGGUAAAGGCGAGGAAGUCUUGGCUGGCGUUGCUGACUCACAGUCGCCAUCCAUCUGGACACAAAGAGAGACCUGUGGGAGUCGUAGAGGGUACUGUUAGCCCCGGUCCAUGCAGGGGGUUCAGCCGAGCCCAAGACUCAAAGCUGCUUUCCUUUCAGGAUUUGUAGUAACGUAAGGUGAUAAUGGCCAAAAGUGGUUCUCUCUCAUUAAACCAACCAGUAAAAGCGUAUCCUAUUUUUUUGCACAAGGUGUUUCAUUUUCGUUUUUAUGGGAAACCAAGGGAAAAGCACAUUGCGAUCCAUUCAGUGUUUAACUGUCGUGGCUCAUUUUCUGUUCGUUAGCACUUGUGUGACAAAAGAGCUCAGAUCCGACUUCUCCUAUGUGUCACUUAUUCCAAGAACCCAACUAUGCCCUUAGGUAGAAAGAUUUGACUCGUGUGUCUACUAGCCAACAGGCAGAGCAGGGUUGAAAAAAAUAUCAGCUCCCAAAGGGCCCAUGUGUCUACAUCAUCAGUUACUGUCAUGCACCACAUUUGUGUGCAGAUACCAAAAGAGGAGGAAAGAAGAAAAAAAUUAAUGUGUGGGAGCUGCACGUUUACAUGUUUUGAGCUAUGCUUCAAACACAACUGGAAAGCCAUCAAUCUUCAAAGGCCUCAAAAAUACUUUUAUAGUAACAAGUGCACGACUUUAGUUGGGUUAUUCAAGAUGGCACAAAAAGGUUUCCGCAGAGGUGGUAUGCUGUGCUUUUGGCGCAAGUGGUGGGGGGAUGGGGUGGGGGUGGAAUUUUUUUCUCACUCUAAUGACUUCCUAUUGGAAAGGCAUUGACAGCCAGGGACAGGAGCCAGGGUGGGGGUAGUUUUGUGGGAAAGCAGAACUGAAGUUAGCUUAAGCAUAAAAACAAAGAAAAAUCUUCGCUUUUCAUGUAUGUGGAAUCCAAGAAUAACCAUAGGCUCUACCAGACCAGAAGGGUAAGGAUGGACACUAAAAUGAAACAAAUACCAAGGUAUUCCUUCUGCUGCAGCCUGGAGACCACCGAGAGUCGAGCUGGGGCACACACACACCUGGCCGGGACCCGGCAGGGACAAGGCGGGCCGUGGCCUCCUCCACCAAGUCUCUCUAGACAAUUCAGGGCCUGCUUUCCCCAGCUCCAUGCAUGGCUGGACUGGUGAUUCCAGGGUGCAGAAGGGAUUCAUAUUCCCAGAACGCUUUAAGUGUACACCUGCAGGAUAAAGAGAUACCGGUUACAUUAUUAAAUGAUUCUAGGGAUUCACUGGGGGAUAUUUUUGUUGCUUUUACUUUCAUGGUUAGAGCUACAAAGAACAGUGAUUUUUUUUUUUUCUCCCUUCCCCAUUCAGAAACAUUAUACAUUGGGCCAUUUUUCUUUCUCCCAAAGAAGAUUCAUGGAUAGUCAGACUGAACUGUGUGCAACAGGAAAAGUCAAAAGGGAAAAGGUAGCUGAUGAGGUUACAUGGUUACAUGUUCUACAUCAUGCAUAGUAGCUUGAAAUCUAGUCUGGAGAAAACUGGAUCAAGAUUCUAGCCCACUGGAGUUGCAAGGAAUGAGAGGCAAAAAUUCUAAAGAUUUGGGUUAUAUUUUCAACUUGGGGGACAGAGAGAAAUGGAGAGCAGGAAUUACAGUUCCAACAAACAUCAUGAUAGUCUGGUAGUCAAGACAGAGAUUAAGUAAAACAGGUUUUACUGUUUAGCUGAGUUCAGUUAAUACAAAAUGUACAUAAAACGUUAGUCCUUUGAGACUGACAUGAUUAAUGAUCAGUGUGGUGGGAAAUGAUGUAGUUAUUGUACACAAGCACUUGCAAACUCUUUAUCCCUAUUUCUUUAAAACAAAAUAAGGUGAAAUACGAAGUCCUUGGUCUGAUAUAAAGCCCCUAUUGGAUUCUUCGGAUGCGUAAAAGAAAUUGCCUGUUUCAGCCAGAAGACUGGUGAAAACACAUACAUCAGACUAUGUUGUGAGCCAGGUUGAUUUUUUAUUUUAUUAUAUGCAGGUGAGUGUUGAAACUGUUAAAAUUCCAAUUUGUUUUCAUUCAGUAUUAGUUUAGUUCUAAAUAUAGCAAACCCCAUCCAGGUGCUAUCAGAUGACCAGUUACUGCUUAGUUAACUAGGUGUAAAGUUUUACAUAUACAUUAAUGUCAAUAGUUUAUUACAAGUUGUGUAAAAUGGACUCUAGUUUAAUAAUGGGGGAAAAAAGAUUAGGUUGCUCCUGAAACUGACUGUAGAGCAUGUAAAAUGAUUUUACUGGAUUCUGUUCAACUGUAAUCAAUGAAAAAGAUGUACGUUGUAGACAAAGUUGCAGAAUUAAAAAAAGAAAUCUGCUUUUAAUUUAUUCUUUUUGUAUUAAGAAUUUGUAUAGUACCUUUACAUUUUGCAAAACAGUGUUGUCAACACUUAUUAAAGCAUUUUCAAAAUGAAAAGA